AUUCCAGCUGCGACUGCUGAGGGAGAAAAUGAUGCCCAGGUUGGGCUCCCCGGCCCACCGGCCGAGGAGAGGCCUGCGCUGCACACGCGCAGACCGAGCAUCCGCGUCAAGAGGCGAAGAGAGCGCGCGCUCCCCACGUCCUGCGCUCCUGGCUGCCGGGCAUUCGUCUCAGCCGUGACUCUCGCCAGGCCGGGGCUGGCGCGCCCACGUCUGAAGAGCGAUGCCCCGGGAGAUCAUCACCCUGCAGCUGGGCCAGUGCGGCAACCAGAUUGGGUUCGAGUUCUGGAAACAGCUGUGCGCCGAGCAUGGUAUCAGCCCCGAGGGCAUCGUGGAGGAAUUCGCCACCGAGGGCACUGACCGCAAGGACGUCUUUUUCUACCAGGCAGACGAUGAGCACUACAUCCCCCGGGCCGUGCUGCUGGACUUGGAACCCCGGGUGAUCCACUCCAUCCUCAACUCCCCCUAUGCCAAGCUCUACAACCCAGAGAACAUCUACCUGUCGGAACAUGGAGGAGGAGCUGGCAACAACUGGGCCAGCGGAUUCUCCCAGGGUGAGAAAAUUCAUGAAGACAUCUUUGACAUCAUAGACCGAGAAGCAGAUGGAAGUGACAGUUUGGAGCUCCAGAACAGCUCCAGAGUGAUAAAGGGCUUCGUGCUGUGUCACUCCAUCGCUGGGGGUACGGGUUCUGGCCUGGGCUCCUACCUCCUGGAGCGACUGAAUGACAGGUACCCCAAGAAGCUAGUGCAGACUUAUUCAGUGUUUCCCUACCAGGACGAGAUGAGCGACGUAGUGGUUCAGCCCUACAAUUCACUCCUGACACUCAAGAGGCUGACGCAGAACGCAGAUUGUGUGGUGGUGCUGGACAACACAGCCCUGAACCGGAUUGCCACAGACCGCCUGCACAUCCAGAACCCGUCCUUCUCCCAGAUCAACCAGCUGGUGUCCACCAUCAUGUCGGCCAGCACCACCACCCUGCGCUACCCCGGCUACAUGAACAAUGACCUCAUCGGCCUCAUCGCCUCGCUCAUUCCCACCCCACGGCUCCACUUCCUCAUGACCGGCUACACCCCGCUCACUACAGACCAGUCAGUGGCCAGCGUGAGGAAGACCACGGUCCUGGAUGUCAUGAGGCGGCUGCUGCAGCCCAAGAACGUGAUGGUGUCCACAGGCCGAGACCGCCAGACCAACCACUGCUACAUCGCCAUCCUCAACAUCAUCCAGGGAGAGGUGGACCCCACCCAGGUCCACAAGAGCCUGCAGAGGAUCCGGGAACGGAAGUUGGCCAACUUCAUCCCGUGGGGCCCCGCCAGCAUCCAGGUGGCCCUGUCGAGGAAGUCUCCCUACCUGCCCUCGGCCCACCGGGUCAGCGGGCUCAUGAUGGCCAACCACACCAGCAUCUCCUCGCUCUUUGAAAGUUCCUGCCAGCAGUUUGACAAGCUGCGGAAGCGGGAUGCCUUCCUCGAGCAGUUCCGUAAGGAGGACAUGUUCAAGGACAACUUUGAUGAGAUGGACAGGUCUAGGGAGGUUGUUCAGGAGCUCAUUGAUGAGUACCAUGCGGCCACCCAGCCAGACUACAUUUCCUGGGGCACCCAGGAGCAGUGAUUUCCCUCCCCACUACUCCUUCUCCUUCUAGAUGGUAACCACAGCCUCGACCAUGCCUGCUCCCUCUGACCCAGCUUCACCUCAUGGACAACCCUUCUUGGUUCAUCUCCAGCCCGUGAGCUGGUCCUGCUUCCUCCCUUCCAUGCCCUAACUUUUAAUAUGCUUGUUCAGCUCUAAUAAAGUAAUAAAGCUUGGUUGUCAGUAUA